ACAGCCCGCGCAGUUGCCGCGGAUCGUGCUGAGCCCCGCGAGCCGAGGCAGCGCAGCCUAGGGAGGGGGCUGCCCCGGCCCCCUCCUGCAGUCCCGGCCCCUAGAGGCUCGGCCUUCCUCGCAGGAAGGCGAAGUCCCCGGUGCCAGGUCCGGGGACCAGCAGCCGAGAACGCCCGGGUCCCGGAGCCAACAGGCUCCGAGUGCCCUCGCUCCCCCGCGCCUUCCCGGAGCCCCGCCAGCCCCCGAGGUGCAGGAAGGUCCCGCGGACGGAGCGGGCCUGCCGGCGUUCAGUGGGGUUCUUGGUGAAGCACUUGGCACGCAUCGGAGCUCAUUACUCCUCAUCGUGGUCCUGUAAGGAAGUUUGAGGCUGAGACCCGAAAAGACCUGGGUGCAAGCCUCCAGGCACCCUGAAGGGAGUGGGCUGAGGGCUGGCCCAAGCUCCCUCCUCUCCCUCUGUAGAGCCUAGGAUGCCCCUCUGCUGCAGCGGCUCCUGAGCUCAUGGAGCCCUCAGCCACCCCAGGGGCCCAGAUGGGGGUCCCCCCUGGCAGCAGAGAGCCGUCCCCUGUGCCUCCAGACUAUGAAGAUGAGUUUCUCCGCUAUCUGUGGCGCGAUUAUCUGUACCCAAAACAGUAUGAGUGGGUCCUCAUCGCAGCCUAUGUGGCUGUGUUCGUCGUGGCCCUGGUGGGCAACACGCUGGUCUGCCUGGCCGUGUGGCGGAACCACCACAUGAGGACAGUCACCAACUACUUCAUUGUCAACCUGUCCCUGGCUGACGUUCUGGUGACUGCUAUCUGCCUGCCGGCCAGCCUGCUGGUGGACAUCACUGAGUCCUGGCUGUUCGGCCAUGCCCUCUGCAAGGUCAUCCCCUAUCUACAGGCUGUGUCCGUGUCAGUGGCAGUGCUAACUCUCAGCUUCAUCGCCCUGGACCGCUGGUAUGCCAUCUGCCACCCACUAUUGUUCAAGAGCACAGCCCGGCGGGCCCGUGGCUCCAUCCUGGGCAUCUGGGCUGUGUCGCUGGCCAUCAUGGUGCCCCAGGCUGCAGUCAUGGAAUGCAGCAGUGUGCUGCCUGAGCUAGCCAACCGCACACGGCUCUUCUCAGUCUGUGAUGAACGCUGGGCAGAUGACCUCUAUCCCAAGAUCUACCACAGUUGCUUCUUUAUUGUCACCUACCUGGCCCCACUGGGCCUCAUGGCCAUGGCCUAUUUCCAGAUAUUCCGCAAGCUCUGGGGCCGCCAGAUCCCCGGCACCACCUCAGCACUGGUGCGGAACUGGAAGCGCCCCUCAGACCAGCUGGGGGACCUGGAGCAGGGCCUGAGUGGAGAGCCCCAGCCCCGGGCCCGCGCCUUCCUGGCUGAAGUGAAGCAGAUGCGUGCACGGAGGAAGACAGCCAAGAUGCUGAUGGUGGUGCUGCUGGUCUUCGCCCUCUGCUACCUGCCCAUCAGCGUCCUCAAUGUCCUUAAGAGGGUGUUCGGGAUGUUCCGCCAAGCCAGUGACCGCGAAGCUGUCUACGCCUGCUUCACCUUCUCCCACUGGCUGGUGUACGCCAACAGCGCUGCCAACCCCAUCAUCUACAACUUCCUCAGUGGCAAAUUCCGGGAGCAGUUUAAGGCUGCCUUCUCCUGCUGCCUGCCUGGCCUGGGUCCCUGCGGCUCUCUGAAGGCCCCUAGUCCCCGCUCCUCUGCCAGCCACAAGUCCUUGUCCUUGCAGAGCCGAUGCUCCAUCUCCAAAAUCUCUGAGCAUGUGGUGCUCACCAGCGUCACCACAGUGCUGCCCUGAGCGAGGGCUGCCCUGGAGGCUCCGGCUCGGGGGAUCUGCCCCUACCCCUCAUGGAAAGACAGCUGGAUGUGGUGAAAGGCUGUGGCUUCAGUCCUGGGUUUCUGCCUGUGUGACUCUGGAUAAGUCACUUCCUCUGUCUGAGCUUGUGUCCCCUAAGCAGGGUUGAUGUGAGGAUUAAGCAUGCUGAAGCAAGUGGAAAGCUCCUUGUAAACUGUGAAGUGUUGUGGACAUGAUUAUUGUUGUACUUCUCUCAUUUGGCCAUACCCCACAGUAUAAUCUGUCCCCAUCCUCCUUCCAGAGCUUGGUCAUCCUCCUAAAGACCCCUUUCCUACCCAAUUACAGGCCUUCCCUGGAGUCUGCUCUAAAGGUCCCAACAGGCAUUUCCAUCUUGUUCCAUGGCUCCCUGAAGCCCAGGGCUGCACUUGGCCAGCUGUUCUGAUGCCUGUGUGAACUAAUCUGGGCCCAGCCUUUCUCCAGCGGGCCACGAGCACAGCCCCACCCUAACCAGGUGCCAAGGGCACACACCACAGACCCGACCUUGUUGGCUUUGUGGUGUGAUAAAACACUCUCCAUGGCCACUUGGCAGAGAGGCCAGCAGCCCGAAGCAACUGUAAUUAAAAGCCUGGCACUGAAUGUUCCCUUUCCUUGUCAUUGCACAAAAUCUGUGCUGCUUAGGUUAGGAGCAGAAGAAGGUGGGGAAGCUGGGGGGAGGGAAGACAAGAAGGCACUAGAAUGCUCUUAUCUGCUGACCUCCCACCCCCACCACACGGGAUCCCAGAUGGACUCAGCCAGGCCUCGGCACACGUGGUGCUGCCUCCUCAUGCGGUGCCAAUCCUGUGACGCCGGGACCUCACCCCUCGACACAACUGUCUGCUCACAGGCCCAGUGGCCUGGGGAAGGAUAAAAAGAGAAAGCCACAGACUUGGCCAGACAUGCUCCGUCUGCCACCGAGAUUUUAAGGCUGCCAAAGGCCCUGAGCCUUGUUGCCAGAGAAGGACGUGGAGUGCAGCCUGAAGUGCUACUCUGCUGAGAGGAACAGGGACAUCUGGCAGGGGCCAGCUCUGCUAUGCAUACCACCAGGUCUGCUUAACUUGAUUAAUAGAGCUGUGGGCUCCCUCUGACCUCAACCGUCAAGAACGUGGGCAGAGCCCUGGUGCUGCCAGGGGCCCAGCCCAGGAGUGUUGAAGCACUGCUCCUCCUAAGCACCCCGCUUUACCCAGAGCAGGUGGAAUGUGUGGUCUAAGUAUGCCACCUGCUCUCCACACGACUUACCAGCCCAGCUCUCUGUGGACGGGGCAGAGCUCUAGCUGCUGCCAGGAGGAUGGGCUCUCCUGCCCAUUCCACACUCCCACUGGCCUUAGGAUCCAAAGCGGUUGGCACAGUGCAUAGGUAGGCUUGGAGGUGAGUGUGCAGAAUGAGGUAUGAGGGCUGGCCCCCAAGCUCAGAACCAACCGUGCUUACAAGAUCAAUCCAGGUCUUGGGCUCCUCAGCCUCAGCUGAGCACAAAGGUGAGAGACUACAAUUGGCACCAUCGGGUUUCAGCAGACACUUGGUUCAGUGGGAACAAAGAAACAACAGGCGCUGCUCCUAAUGGCUGCACGCUCUGCUGGCUGAACCCAGCACCAUGGGGGGCCUCAGCCCUCCACUCUGGGGGACUCAGAUAAACUGAAGAAAAUUCAGGGGAGGUGACCAGGAUGCCAAGGGCAGAGAUGCUCAGCGAGGGACUGCUCAAGAGCCCAGGGCUAUCUGGCCCAGGGAAGAGAGGACUUGGGGAAAAUGUGGUAUAUAGGGUAGGCUCCACUAUAUAGAGGGUUGGCAUGCAUAAAGGGUGAUGUAUGUCCUGGGUGGCCCACAGAGAAAACCACAGCAAAUGGUGGUGUCUUCAAGAUGGCAGGAUUUAGAAUCCACAUAAGGAAGAUGUUUCUGCCAGUCAUGGAGGAAAUGGGCUGCCUUGAAAGGCACUGAGUUCUUUGCCUUUGGCGAAGCAGAGGCCAGACUCACAUGGGGACUAUGAACGGAAUUUUAGCUCUGGAUGGGGGCUGGCCUCUGGGAACUGGAUUCCAUCUAAUGCGGGGAUUCUAGCACUACAGCAGCCCAGAGGAGAAUGCAACUGACCUGGCUAAGCCCGACACACUGCUGGGCCUCACUGACCUGCAAAACAGUCAUAGUUACUUCCAACUACCCACUGCAGGGAGGAGAGCCCUGCACAGGGCCUCAGAGCUCUUUAUCUCAAAAAGCCAAAAGAUAAUCACCAUUACCCAGAAUAAAGCCCCCUGGCAAACUAGAAUGUCUGGUGUCUUUGGCUUUUGAUUGAAAUGUGGUCAGCUCAUUAGAGACACUCGGUGUAGACUGGGUAUUAUGCUGAUCUAAAGAUCUGACUUGCAAGUACAGAUGUCUGUGCUUAAUAAAAGUGGGGAGAACGUUAUGACUUAAUAAAUGGAGUUUGUCUGGAAGAUAAAACUAGGGCCUGAGAAAAUAGAAAAGGCCAGGCUAUGAAGUUUGAGGUAGCUGCUUUCAACCCAGAAUGCCAGCCCUAAAACUGCUAUGAAAUAGCUUCCUAAAUAGACCUUCAGGCCAUACUGAACUGAACCCGGCAGGCCCCUCAGCUGGCUACCCUAUACUUCAACUUCCCUCUGGCAGUGGAGAGGAGCCCCACAUAGGCAAUGUCCCCCCAAGCUGCUGCUUUCUGCAUGGCGUGGUGUAUAGGAUGUACUUAAAUAGUCACUGAAAGGAUGAGUGGAUGGACCUGUAGCUGAGAAAUCAUGGUGGAAAACAUGGAACUCCAGAGUUUCAUCCUUUUAUUGAAGCUUACAAUUUCACUGGA